GUAAAGAAGUCAUGGCGGCGCUGUGUCGGACCCGUGCUGUGGCUGCCGAGAGCCAUUUUCUGCGAGUGUUUCUCUUCUUCAGGCCCUUUCGGGGUGUAGGCACUGAGAGUGGAUCCGAAAGUGGUAGUUCCAAUGCCAAGGAGCCUAAGACGCGCGCAGGCGGUUUCGCGAGCGCGUUGGAGCGGCACUCGGAGCUUCUACAGAAGGUGGAGCCCCUACAGAAGGGUUCUCCAAAAAAUGUGGAAUCCUUUGCAUCUAUGCUGAGACAUUCUCCUCUUACACAGAUGGGACCUGCAAAGGAUAAACUGGUCAUUGGACGGAUCUUUCAUAUUGUGGAGAAUGAUCUGUACAUAGAUUUUGGUGGAAAGUUUCAUUGUGUAUGUAGAAGACCAGAAGUGGAUGGAGAGAAAUACCAGAAAGGAACCAGGGUCCGGUUGCGGCUAUUAGAUCUUGAACUUACGUCUAGGUUCCUGGGAGCAACAACAGAUACAACUGUACUAGAGGCUAAUGCAGUUCUCUUGGGAAUCCAGGAGAGUAAAGACUCAAGAUCGAAAGAAGAACAUCAUGAAAAAUAAAUGAACUUUGCUUAGUGGAUUGACUCCUUUGCUGAAGUCAGUUAUUCAUCAAGAAUGCAAUUAGACUAAUUGUGAAUAAAUGAUUGAAUGAAGAUAUAAUAAAUAAAAGCUAUAAUUAUAGAUAACUCUUAUUAGAAUUUUCUUUAGCAAUAUUCCCACCCCCCACCCCUUGUUUUGCUCUUAAUGUUUUUUUCCUUUGGUGGGGAUAGUAUACACUGUACUAAGAAAUUGUCAUUCAAUAAAUACGUUUUGAGUGCUGUCUA